UUUUCAGAGACUCGCCUGGCAGAGGCCUGGAGCGUCCUGCUGCGUGGACUGUGGGCACCGAGCCACCAGGAGGUUGUUGAUCUCAUUCUUGCUCACUGGUCCCUGCCAGACUGGUGGUGCCUCUCUACUGUCGGGCAGCCCCACCUCUGUGCUGCCCCAUCCACCUACAGCCCUCAUGCCUGGGCCCAGCUGGAGGUUCUGACAGGGGCCCCCUGGGGUGGCAUGCGGACCCUUCAGGGUGCCCCAGGCGCAGCACAGGUCUCCAGAGACACAGGCACCAGGGCGUUCAGAGCUAGUCCCCUCGCUGCUGUUGACUGUCCUUGAGCAGCCCCAGGGCCGGUUUCUCAACCUCAUUUGCUCACCUGAGCAAUGAAGUGAGGUGGGCUCCUGGAACUGCAGCAGCCACCCCCCGGGGCCAUCGUGAGGCUAAGAAUCCAGUGCAGGGUGAGCAACCAGCGACCGCUACAAGGACAGUGAAGAGCUAGCACCAGGACCUUGGGUAGCCCACCCGCUGGAGGGAGCGUGUGCUGCAAAAAGCAAGAGUGGGCUUUGGAGGCCAACGGAUGGAGCGGAUUCAGUCUGAGGCUGUUCCAGCCCUUGCUUAGGAUCCACCUACCUAGGUCUGGAAAUCGUAUUUCCACUUCAGAUGCCUUCUCAGAGGAUAAAAUAACCCCCGGUGGGGGAGAGUACUGGAAGAGGGCUAAUUCCCCUGGUUUUCUCCCCAUGAGCAUUAGUGUCAGUGUAAUUUUAGAGUGACCCCAGCUAUGUCACGUGUGGCAGGCACAAGAACAGAUGUCAAUGAGCUAUUGCAGAGGUGGACACCCAGAUGUGUGCGCUGGCACACUGGAGGGGCCCGUAGGGUGGCUCUAGACCGCCCCCUCGUGACGGCUUGCCUACCACCUGCAGGCGACGUUGUGGACGUUUACCAGCGGGAGUUCCUGGCGCUGCGCGAUCGGUUGCACGCAGCUGAGCAGGAGAGCCUCAAGCGCUCCAAGGAGCUCAACCUGGUGCUGGACGAGAUCAAGAGGGCCGUGUCAGAAAGGCAGGCGCUGCGAGACGGAGACGGCAAUCGCACCUGGGGCCGCCUAACAGAGGACCCCCGAUUGAAGCCGUGGAACGGCUCACACCGGCACGUGCUGCACCUGCCCACCGUCUUCCAUCACCUGCCACACCUGCUGGCCAAGGAGAGCAGUCUGCAGCCCGCGGUGCGCGUGGGCCAGGGCCGCACCGGAGUGUCGGUGGUGAUGGGCAUCCCGAGCGUGCGGCGCGAGGUGCACUCGUACCUGACUGACACUCUGCACUCGCUCAUCUCCGAGCUGAGCCCGCAGGAGAAGGAGGACUCGGUCAUCGUGGUGCUGAUCGCCGAGACUGACUCACAGUACACUUCGGCAGUGACAGAGAACAUCAAGGCCUUGUUCCCCACGGAGAUCCAUUCUGGGCUCCUGGAGGUCAUCUCACCCUCCCCCCACUUCUACCCUGACUUCUCCCGCCUCCGAGAGUCCUUUGGGGACCCCAAGGAGAGAGUCAGGUGGAGGACCAAACAGAACCUCGAUUACUGCUUCCUCAUGAUGUACGCGCAGUCCAAAGGCAUCUACUACGUGCAGCUGGAGGAUGACAUCGUGGCCAAGCCCAACUACCUGAGCACCAUGAAGAACUUUGCACUGCAGCAGCCUUCAGAGGACUGGAUGAUCCUGGAGUUCUCCCAGCUGGGCUUCAUUGGUAAGAUGUUCAAGUCGCUGGACCUGAGCCUGAUUGUAGAGUUCAUUCUCAUGUUCUACCGGGACAAGCCCAUCGACUGGCUCCUGGACCAUAUUCUGUGGGUGAAAGUCUGCAACCCCGAGAAGGAUGCGAAGCACUGUGACCGGCAGAAAGCCAACCUGCGGAUCCGCUUCAAACCGUCCCUCUUCCAGCACGUGGGCACUCACUCCUCGCUGGCUGGCAAGAUCCAGAAACUGAAGGACAAAGACUUUGGAAAGCAGGCGCUGCGGAAGGAGCAUGUGAACCCGCCAGCAGAGGUGAGCACGAGCCUGAAGACAUACCAGCACUUCACCCUGGAGAAAGCCUACCUGCGCGAGGACUUCUUCUGGGCCUUCACCCCUGCCGCGGGGGACUUCAUCCGCUUCCGCUUCUUCCAACCUCUAAGACUGGAGCGGUUCUUCUUCCGCAGUGGGAACAUCGAGCACCCGGAGGACAAGCUCUUCAACACGUCUGUGGAGGUGCUGCCCUUCGACAACCCUCAGUCAGACAAGGAGGCCCUGCAGGAGGGCCGCACCGCCACCCUCCGGUACCCUCGGAGCCCCGACGGCUACCUCCAGAUCGGCUCCUUCUACAAGGGAGUGGCAGAGGGAGAGGUGGACCCAGCCUUCGGCCCUCUGGAAGCACUGCGCCUCUCGAUCCAGACGGACUCCCCUGUGUGGGUGAUUCUGAGCGAGAUCUUCCUGAAAAAGGCCGACUAAGCUGCGGGCUUCUGAGGGUACCCUGUGGCCAGCCCUGAAGCCCACAUUUCUGGGGGUGUCGUCACUGCCGUCCCCGGAGGGCCAGAUACGGCCCCGCCCAAAGGGUUCUGCCUGGCGUCGGGCUUGGGCCGGCCUGGGGUCCGCCGCUGGCCCGGAGGCCCUAGGAGCUGGUGCUGCCCCCGCCCGCCGGGCCGCGGAGGAGGCAGGCGGCCCCCACACUGUGCCUGAGGCCCGGAACCGUUCGCACCCGGCCUGCCCCAGUCAGGCCGUUUUAGAAGAGCUUUUACUUGGGCGCCCGCCGUCUCUGGCGCGAACACUGGAAUGCAUAUACUACUUUAUGUGCUGUGUUUUUUAUUCUUGGAUACAUUUGAUUUUUUCACGUAAGUCCACAUAUACUUCUAUAAGAGCGUGACUUGUAAUAAAGGGUUAAUGAAGUGUGUGCCUCAAA